CCUGUUAGGCGAGAGCUGCGAAAGGCGAGAGCUGCGAAGGGCCAGGUGUCGGGCGCUGUUUCUCGUUUUCAUCAUAUAGACAAAACAGCCCUGCUGCAAAGAUGGUCAACGUACCUAAAACCCGAAGAACCUUCUGUAAGAAGUGUGGCAAGCAUCAGCCUCACAAAGUGACACAGUAUAAGAAGGGCAAGGAUUCUUUGUAUGCCCAGGGAAGGAGGCGCUAUGAUCGGAAGCAGAGUGGCUAUGGUGGGCAGACAAAGCCAAUUUUCCGGAAGAAGGCUAAGACCACAAAGAAGAUUGUGCUAAGGCUGGAAUGUGUUGAGCCUAACUGCAGAUCCAAGAGGAUGCUGGCCAUUAAGAGAUGCAAGCAUUUUGAACUGGGAGGAGAUAAGAAGAGAAAGGGCCAAGUGAUCCAGUUCUAAACUUUGGGAUAUUUUUCUUCAAUUUUGAAGAGAAAAUGGUGAAGCCAUAGAAAAGUUACCCGAGGGAAAAUAAAUACAGUGAUAUUCUUACGCAAACUUUUUGUGGUUUUUACUUAUAAAUAGAAUUCCAUGUUUAGUGUAGUCCCACCUCAAACUUUACUAACAAGUUUAUAUAUGUAUGAAGGGAAAAUACUACUUUACUACUUUUUGUUUUCUGGUCAAUUUCAAAUGUUGAAUGAAUUCAUAAACAUUGA